CUUUGUAGUUUAUCAUUCUUUGGGCUGCGGUUGUCAAGGAUUCAGAGCAGAUGUGAUCUGCGCUAGGUGGCAUCUCCUCUCACGGAUGCCUCGGUGAGCUUCGGAGUCGGGCUACCGCUGAGGGGCUUCGGAAGGGCCAGUCUGUGCACUGCGACCUGGACUGGGUGUGGGGAUUUGGCGGCAGGGUCUUCUUGGCCAGAGAUGGGCCGGGCAGGUGAAGGGCAGAGGAGGUUGCUCCGCAGCCUGGAAGGGCUUUGUUAACCAAAAGUCAGCGUCGUUGCCCCUACCCCUUUCCCCCACCCUAUGUCUGUUCCUGAGCUCUUCAACCUCUCUGCCCUGUACUGAUGGCACUCUGAACUCUCCGUAUCUGCAUCUUAGGAUUCAAAUAGAUUCGGAUAUGAAGAAAUGUUUGUAUUUUCCGAUGUCUUAUUCUCUACUGUGGACUUAUUUUAAAGAAUGAGCAGGGAUAGUUUUAAACUAUGCCACAGCCUUUCUUAGUCUAACUCACAUAGUAUAAAGGCUCUUGCUGCUAUCGAAUUUUUUAAAAGAAUAAAUAGCAUCUACUAUGUGCCAGCCCAGCACUGUUCUAAGCACUUUACAAAUAUUAUCUGCUUCUCAUAACUCUAUGAGAUAGACACUAUUAUUAUGUAGACUACACCCCACCUCUCUGUCCCGCCCCUUUUUAAAAUUAACAUACAAGAAGAAAAUGAAGUUAGUAACUUGCCCAAGGUCGUAGAGCGAGUAAGGGGUGUAGGCAGGAUUCAAAUACAGGCAAUUUGGCUCCAGACUCCAUUUUCUUAAAACCUUUGCUAUGCUAACUCCACUCUGUUCCUAUAUUAGCUUUACAGCUAUAACCCGGGAAGUUACUUCGCUCAUUUGAAUCCCGUCCUUCUUUUGUACCUCAGUAGUCCUGGGCUUCUAGUUAGGAUUUGAUUGGAGAGAAUAUAUCUGAAGACGUAUAUCUUUCAGUGUUUCUGCAAACCUGAUGAAACAGCCGUUUUAUUGGUUUGUGUGCAUGUUUUCACCCACUCAUCUUGUUCUUUGAGCAAUAGAAAAAGAUUACAGUCUUGGCCCUAAGGGAAAGUAGCAACUAUUAAUUAAACUACCAUUGUACCAAAAUUGUACAUUAUCUUAUUAAAAGAUUAAUUUGCAUGUUUAUAUGCCAGGUUUUGUGCAAAAACACUUUGUAUGCAUUAUCUCAUUUAAUAUUCUCAACAAGUUGGCAAGGCAGUUGUUGACCUCAUUUCAUAUAUGAGCUUGAGGCUUAGAAAAAUCAACUAACUUGCCCAAGAUCACUGCGUUAAAAUUCACAGAUGGCCUGGCACUAUGGUUCAUGCCUGUAAUCCCAGCACUUUGGGAGGCCGAGGUGGGCAGAUCACGUGAGGUCGGGAGUUCGAGACCAGCCUGACCCAUAUGGUGAAACUCCAUCCUACUAAAAAUGCAAAAAUGAGCCAGGAGUGGUGGUGGGUCCCUGUAAUCCCAGCUACUCCGGAAGCUGAGGCAGGAGGAUUGCUUGAACCUGGGAGGCAGAGGUUGCAAGUGAGCCGAGAUCGCACCACUGCACUCCCGCCUGGGCAACAAAAGCAAGACUCUGUCUCAAAAAAAAAAAAAAAAAAAUUAACAACCAGAUCUGCCUGUGUUCUCUGCUAUCUCAUACUACCUUCUGCUUGUCUAAGGUAAAUAAAAUAUAUGGGCUUAUAUCAACUCUAUGUGUGCACAUGUGUAUACAUGUGUAUAUACGAUUGCAAAUGCAUAGAAAAGGACACAUUCCAGUAUUUAAGACUGUUUAUUUCAGGGUAAUAGAACUUGGUGAAAGAAUUCUAUAUUCCUCUCUACUUUUUGGAUUUAAAAAAGGUUCUGAAGAGAAGUAAUGGUACAAGAUAAAUUGUGACUGAGGGUGAAAGGUGGGACUCAUACAGUACAUGACAUAUGAGUGGGCAGUUGGAAGAGGGUGAGCUGAAAUGGGUAAAGAAGACUUCAGAGAGGAUGUGAGAUUUGAAUCAAGCUGCAGAGAUUGGGUAAGGUUCGAAUAAGGGAAGAAGGCAAGACCAAGCUCAUGGCGCAGGGAUGAGAAACGCCUGAUUAGAAUAAUGAGAAGAAAAACCUGACUGGAGCUGAGAGUUUUUGCUUGUGGAAUAGAGGAAACCAAGAGUGGAGCCAGACAACAGAAGCUAAAGGUCUGACUGGUUUUAAACUGUGCUUGAGAGUUUGGGAAUUCAUCCAAUUAGUGAGGAGCCAUAGAUGGUGUCAGCGGAGGUGAGGGUCGUGGGAUAUAUGAUGAUAAAGGCACAUUUGUAUUACAUGCUGCUUAGUCUUCACCUACGUGCAUGUCCUUGGUUAACAGCAUCCUUCCAUGAGGAUGAUGGUAGAUUUGGGGGUGUUCAGCUUGCUGAGGCUCUAGGAGGAACCAACUUUAAAAUGCAGAUGUAUUUUUUAAGGUAAGACUUAUUAUGCUAAUUAUAUACCUGGCAUAUACAUUGAGGUUGUGAUCCUGAAUGGAAGAUUAGGAACUCUAUGUUUGUGACGAGGAGGGCAGUAUUACAAAAAACUGGGGAAGCCUUUUGGAGACACCAGGUUCAAAGAAGAACUCAGGUAUGCUGGUGCAAGGAUCUGGGUAUUAAGGCCACCAGAUAAAAGCAAAAUCAGGUGAAGGAAAGCAAAAAUGAACCCAGAGUAUACAGAGAAAAUAGGGAAAUUUGUAUUUGGGAAACUGUAUAAAGAUUUGAAACACCACAUCCCAGAAAUGAAUUUUUCUGGGCAGAGCUCUAAGCUUCAGCUGCAUUGCCUUUGAAUAGAAAAACUUUGACUUGAAACCAAGCGGCACAGGUGGUAAAUAAGAAAAAGACAUUUUCGGACCCUAAAAGAUUGAAAAAACAAGAAAGCAUAAGUGGCUGUUUCAUCCUUUGAAUCCAUGGUACGUUUAUUGAGUAAUGUGAGAGUACAUAUUCUGGAUUUAGCUAUUUGAUAUUUCUACCACAAAACUUUCUUACCCUAGAACCAAUUCAGCAGAUCAUGUUUCAAGCCAUGAUGAUCUCUUCCCUGGAUGAUUAUCAUAGCAUCCCUCUCUGCCUCCACUUAACCCCAAGGUCAUUGACACAGCGGCUAGAGUUAUGCUUUUGUGUUAAAUGGAAGUAAAAUUUUGUUACCCCUUGGCUCAAAAAUCCCCAGUGGUUUCCAUAUCUCAUAGAAUACAAGUUAGAGCCCUUACCACUGCCUUUCAUGAUCAGUUCCCAAGCUCCCUGCUUUAUCUCCUGUUACUUUCCCUUUUGUUUUCUUUGUUCCAGCCAUUGUUCAACUAGCUAUUACCUGAAGAAUCCAGGUGUGUUCCCACCUGCAAAAAUUUGCACUUGGCAGUUACCUUUGCAUGGAACAGUCUUUCUCCAGAUAGCCAUGUGACUUGCUCCUCACUUCCUUCAGAUCUCGGGGUUUCCAGAAGAAAAGAUCAAGGGAGAAUUAUCAAGAAUAGAUUAUUUUUCUGAAUAGUUAAACCUUUGAUGGCCAUAACCUUGACCCUUCAGACUGCAGAGAUGCAGGAAGGACUUCUGGCAGUGAAGGUAAAGGAGGAAGAGGAGGAACAUUCCUGUGGGCCAGAAUCAGGCCUGUCAAGAAAUAACCCUCAUACCAGAGAGAUCUUUCGUAGACGCUUCAGGCAGUUCUGCUAUCAGGAGUCCCCUGGGCCCCGGGAGGCUCUUCAAAGACUCCAGGAGCUCUGCCAUCAGUGGCUGAGACCAGAGAUGCACACCAAGGAGCAGAUCCUAGAGCUGCUGGUGCUGGAGCAGUUCCUGACUAUCCUGCCUGAGGAGCUCCAGGCCUGGGUCAGACAGCACCGUCCUGUGAGUGGAGAGGAGGCAGUGACUGUGCUGGAGGAUUUGGAGAGAGAGCUGGAUGACCCAGGAGAGCAGGUCCUGAGCCAUGCUCAUGAACAGGAAGAGUUUGUAAAGGAGAAGGCAACUCCAGGAGCAGCUCAGGAGUCAUCAAAUGACCAAUUCCAAACCUUGGAAGAGCAACUUGGGUAUAAUUUGCGAGAGGUGUGCCCAGUUCAAGAGAUUGAUGGCAAGGCUGGGACUUGGAAUGUGGAGUUAGCCCCAAAGAGGGAGAUUUCUCAGGAAGUGAAAUCUCUUAUACAAGUUCUUGGAAAACAGAAUGGUAAUAUUACUCAGAUUCCUGAGUAUGGAGAUACCUGUGACCGUGAGGGCAGAUUGGAAAAGCAAAGGGUGAGCUCUUCAGUGGAGAGACCCUAUAUCUGUAGUGAAUGUGGAAAAAGCUUCACCCAGAAUUCCAUCCUUAUCGAGCACCAGAGAACACACACAGGUGAGAAGCCUUAUGAAUGUGAUGAGUGUGGGCGGGCCUUCAGCCAGAGGUCAGGCCUAUUCCAGCACCAGAGACUCCACACUGGGGAGAAGCGCUACCAGUGCAGUGUUUGUGGCAAAGCCUUCAGCCAGAAUGCCGGGCUUUUCCAUCACCUCAGAAUUCACACUGGGGAGAAGCCUUACCAGUGCAAUCAGUGCAAUAAGAGUUUUAGUCGACGUUCAGUCCUCAUUAAGCAUCAGAGAAUUCACACUGGAGAGAGACCUUAUGAAUGUGAAGAAUGUGGCAAGAACUUCAUUUACCAUUGCAACCUAAUCCAGCAUCGGAAAGUCCACCCAGUGGCUGAAUCAAGCUAGCUCCUUGGAACAGACACUUACACUUGGAGCCCUGAGACCCACUGUAGGCAUCUGCAAACAACAGCAACAACAAAGUGGGAUGGAAAGAAAAAAGAACAAAAUAUAAGAACAUAAAAAAGAAUCAGACAGAAGGUAAAAUUAGAUGCUAAAACUCUAGAUUGGGCAAAAAAUGUUGACCAAAGGAAAAAUAAAAAGAUAGAUGCAGAGACAGAGUGUUGCCAAGAAACAUGCUUCAUCUUCAUAAUAAUUAUUAGAAAUCUCUCUUAUUUAUCAACUGGUCCAAGUUUUUAGAUACUAUUGUCUUAAGCAGUGAAAAUCUCACUGCCUUUUACUCCUCACACUUUUUAUUACUUUCCAUAAAAUGGAGGACAGGGAGAAAAGCAGUCUAUAAACCACUGUGAUUUUUAGAUCUCCUUGAACCUAUCCCCAUUUUUCUAUGCCAACUGCCAAUGGGCAGUGUUGAAAGCACUAUUUCUUGAUGAUAGCUGCACUAGAAUCACCUGGGUUGUUGGUUUGAAGUGCAGUUUUCUCAGCCCCACCCCAGACCUACUGAAUCAGUUUCUGAGGCAGAGCCUGAAAAUCUGUAUCUAAUUAGCAUAUUAGUGGUCCACACACAUAAGGUAACUAUAUAAUUUAUUGUCCAAUCUGGGACACUUGAAAAUGAAAAGGAGUGCUGUUAAUAAUUACACCAAGACAACAGGUAUAAACCAGGAGGUACGGUCCCCAUACUAAUAAUUUUUGCAAUAGGCAGUAUUUUUUCAACCAAGCAUAUAGAAAAGACAGAGAAUCAGAAAGAUUACAAUGUUCUGUCAUGAAAGCUAAGGCAGAAUAUAUAUGAAAAAGGCUGUUGGAGACUUAGGUGUAGCCACCUAGCCUGGUAACCCCCAGUAAUAGAUCUAUUGGAUUAGGAAAGAAAGGAUGGGAUAAUAUGUCUGCACAAACAAAACAGAGGGCCCCCCCAUCCCGCCCCUAAUUAAGACAAACCCAUUGUUAACAUAACUAGUUACCUAAGAUUAACCUAUUGAGUGAAUGGUUUACCAGACAAGAUGGACAACAUCCUGGAAGCACAGGAGUGUUUCAGUGGUAUAGGGACCGAUGGAGUACAGUGUUCAACCUUAUACUGUAGAAGAAAGUGAGAAGAUAGAGUACUGGAUCAGAGCUUGCAGUGUUAAGGCAAACAGUGAGCCAUUUUAAGCAGGUAGUCGGAUGAAGGGGAAGGGGGCAGAUAUUGUACCAAGUAGUUUCAUAAUUUAUCACAUUCACUCCACAUCAUUUGUUGGCUGUGGAGGAGUCCUCUUGCCACUUGAUGGUACCAAAGACAGCUGACCCUGCCUUAAGUGUGUCAAUAGAUCUUCAUAGCUAUUCAGCAAUUGACUCAAGAUCAUUGACUGCAGGGGUGGGGGUGGUGGUGGCCUCCCCUCAUCACCCCUGACUUCUGCUAAUUCAUUGUAGAGGGGUAUGUAGUCAGGGAUCUAUAAGCCCCAAACUUGCUAGUGGUUAAGUUACUCGGGGGGACCUGAUUUAUUUAAACAGGUUUAAAACAAUGGAGAACAAGCCAACAUCUUCCCCGUUUUCCUCAGGUGGGUGUUGAUUAUUGCAUUUGACCCUUGGGGGCAGAGUGAAGGUAAUUGGACAAUUUGUGUGGUACAGAUAAUACCAGACCUGGGGUUGGUUGGUUGGUUGGUUGUUUUGUUUGGAAAGCCCUUUAUCUUCUGAGAGACAUGACUAGGGCUGUGGGAGGAGCUCUGAGUGUGCCUGUGCCUAGACUCCUACACCCCCAUCAGCCAUCCCAGGAUCUUGGUUGGGCUCUAAGGUGCUCGUUGGGGCCGAAUUGAGGAAUCUCCCUGAGGAUAGAGGGAAAGACCCUGAUGCCUGAGACCCUGGAGGACCCGGGACCUAGGGAACGGAGGACACGGAGGAUCCAGUGCGAGCAGUCAAGUGUCUUCAGCAGGGGAGAGAGAGAAGUCAGCCCAGACUGAGUGGCUGCUGGACACAAGAGGUUACGACCCCUGUCGGCCUCAGCCUUUUUGAGGCGGCUUCUGCGCUCACAAAGGUGAGCCAGGUGGUGUGCACAAAUGAACCACUGAGAUUGAUGGAUCCUCCAAGAAUCCUAGAGAGGCGGCAGAGGAGCCGGCCGAAGUGCGUCCUUUCUCCUAGAGAGGUGUUCAGGUUUUAGUGUCCUGGGACUGUGUGUGUAGGCGGUGUCCUGGUCUCUUCUACCCAUGCAAGAUGCUUUAUACUUUCUCAGCGAUCCAGAGAUAACGGUACUCGGAGGGGGUGCUGUUGCCCCCUUUUCCAGGGCUUGCUCGAGUUCCCCUCUUUUACGUAGAUCUCUCAGGAUCAGGAUUUUGUGUUUUGUGUCUGCUCCAUCAGACAUUUCAGAGAUACAGAGAACUGAACAAAGCGCUGUACAGAGCUAGGUCUGUAUGGAUCACCCCCUUCUGAGAUGAGGGCACAGACUUACCAGCAAGGAGGCCUCACCGGAAUCCAUCAGCUGACAGGUCCUUAUGGCCAAAAGCUGGCUUCCGUAUACGUUUUCUGAAUCCUACGGCCGUUUUAACCUGAACAGUUUUUUCAGAGUUUUCAUAAAAAUCCCCUAUGCUAAUGGUCACGAUAUUGUGUAUCUGUAAAGGCUUAGUACUUAAAGAAAAAUACUUUACAUGGUCCCCACAAUUCUGCAAAACAGAGGGAAGUGGUACGUGAAUUUCUCUGGGUAAGAAAACAUUCAGAAGUUAGAACAUUCAAGCAAGCAUUUAUUGAGUGCCACAUAAUGGGCCAGGCUUUAUGUUGCAAAAAUGGGAAUAAGCCAGAUAAAAGGCAUUUCUUACUGUAUAGUGUAAUGGGAAAGACAUGUUGCCUUGAGGAAAAUAAACUUCGUACAUAGGGACUUUGGAGGUGGAACGUUAAAGAUAACUUCCCUGAGUAGGCAAUAGCAGAGCUGUCUCUGUGGACUCUCAGAAGUUGGAUAGCAAAGAGGAAAUGGACCUUGAGGGAUAGUUAUAGUAUGUGAAGGAGGGAUCAGAAAACCAUUUCAGAAAACCACAAGUAAAUGAAGGUGGGUGCAUUCCAGCCUGGGCAACAAGAGUGGCAGAGGUGGGGCAAAGAGAGUAGAGAGUAACUGAAAUAUGCUGAGGAAUUUAAAGUUUAUAGGGUGGUGUGCUUUUCCAUUUUCUUAAUGUCACAGCACAUAAAGAAAAUUUGUAUGCACACUUCCUGGCCACCCCGGUAGCUGAAGAGAUCAGUAUGCUGGUGGUACUCCUAUAAGCCAUUUGAAGCACCCAGUAAACUGUGGCAAUGCACAGUAGUUGGGCAGUUAUAUGCUCUGUCUGGAUUUAAGCAGAGGAGUAAUGUAAUCUUACUAGCUUUCUAGAAAUAUUCUAGAAGUGGUGUGGUGAAUGAAUUGGAAAGGGGCAAAACUGAAAGCAAGGGAGAUAAGAGACUUGUAGUUGUUAAAGAAAGAACCAAAACCAUAAGUUGGUGAAAGUAAGUCACUGGCUAUAGAAAUAAAGAGGGCACCAAGUGGAACUGUGUUAAAGAUUACAGAUUUAACUAGACCUGAUAACUAAUUAGAUUGAUGAAAGUGAGAAAGAAAAGGUACUGAGAGAACUGCCUGUCACACACUAAGUGUAUUCUUUAAAUAAAAUAAAUGUAGCCAGGGAUAAAUAGGCAGGUUUUUGGAUUAAAUUAUUAGGUAAGUGUGGCACAAUUUUAUAAGAGAUGGCUAAUAUUGGAGAAUAAAUUGGUCACAAGGGGAAAAUGAUGAAUUUUUGGUGGUGAGUUGAAGAUGCUUGUAAGACAUACAAGUGAAAAGGUCUAAUGCACCACUGGACUGUAAGGGCCUGGAGCUCCAAAGAAAGAUUGGUAUGAGAGAAUCAGGCUUAGGAGUUUUCAGGUGAAAGCUGAUGUCAUCAAAUGGUUGAGAUUGCCCAGAAUAAAUAUGGGAUGAGAAUAAGGCUGGAUUUCAAUUUAGGAUACUAAACAUUUUUUUUUGAUGGAGUUUUGCUCUUGUUGCCCAUGCUGGAGUGCAAUGGCUCAACCUCAGCUCACCACAACCUCCGCCUCCUGGGUUCAAGUAAUUCUGCCUCAGCCUCCCAAAUAGCUAGGAUUACAGGCACGCGCCAUCACACCCGGCUAAUUUUGUAUUUUUAGUAGAGAUGGGGUUUCUCCAUGUUGGUCAAGCUGGUGUCGAACUCCUGACCUCAGGUGAUCCACCCGCCUCAGCCUCCCAAAGUGUUGGGAUUACAGGUUGGAGCCACCGUGCCCAGCUGGAUACUAGACAUUUUUGACAGGCAGAAUAAGAGCUACGAAGUAGACUAAAUAAUAGUCAUUAGAAACGUAUUUAACAGGUACUUGUAUAAUACAGUCAUGUGCCAUAUAGCGAUGUUUCAGUAAACAGCAGACCACGUGUACAAUAAUAGUUCCAUAAGAUUAUAAUAACAUAUUUUUACUAUACCUUUUCUGUGUUUAGAUAUGUUUAGAUAUACAAAUACUUGGCUUUGUGUUAUAGCUGCCUACAAUAUUCAAUACAGAAACGUGCUGUACAGGUUUGUAGCCUAGGAGCAUUAGGUUAUACACUAUAGCCUAGGUGUAUAGUAGGCUCUACCAUCUAGGUUUGUGGAAGUACAGUCUAUGAUAUUCUCACAAUGAUGAAAUUGCCUAAAGACACAUUUCUCAGAACAUAACCAUGUGAUUAAGCAAUGCAUAACUGUUCUUCCUGAGUGCCAAGCAUUAGGCUAAACGCUACAAAAACCAACUUAUGGAAGAACAACCAGAAGAGUAUAGUGUUUCUUAGAAGAUUGGGAGUAGUUAGCAGUGUUAGGUGCUGCAGGGGCAUCUGGUAGGAAAAGGAUUGAAAAAUACCCACUGGGUUUGUGUACCAAGGGGGCCCUGUUUGUUUAACUUGGGACUGAUAAGUCAGAUGUGAGGUCCCCUGACUGACAUGCACACUAUUCUAAAAUUAAAAAUACUUUUGGGCCAGGCGCGGUGGCUCAUGCCUGUAAUCC